UUAUUUAUUUAUUUAUUUAUUUUUGAGACAGUGUCUCACUCUGUCGCCAGGCUGCAGUGCAAUGGCGGGAUCUCAGCUCACUGCAACCUCUACCUCCCAGGUUCAAGCGAUUCUCCCACCUCGGCUUCCUGAGUAGCGGGGAUUACAGGCACGCACCACCAUGCCAGGCUAAUAUUUGUAUUUUUAGUAGAGAUGGGGUUUCACCAUGUUGGCCAGGCUGGUCUCAAACUCUGACCUCAGGUGAUCUGCCCGCCUUGGCCUCCCAAAGUGCUGGGAUUACAGGCAUGAGCCACGGUGACCAGCCCCACAUGUCAUAAUUUAUUUGCUUAUCAUCUGUCACCUUUGCUGCCCCCUAGUAUGUAAGCUUCAUGAAGGCAGGGACCAUGCAUUACAUGGUUACUGCCAUAUCCUCAGGGUUUGGGGCAGUGCCUACACACAGGAGGUGCUCCUUAAAUGUUUGUUAAGUGAAAUAAUCUGAGGUUGUCAGGUCUUUGUCUUCAACGUUAUUAUUUCUUAUAUUUGUUCAGUGCUUAAUUUUUUUUCAAAGCUCUUGAUGUAGAUUGAAGCUUUUGUCAUUUUUGUCAUAUAGAUGAAACAACUGAGGCACAAAAAUGUGAUCACAAAACCAGAGAGUGGCAGUGCCUACCUGAACAGCUCCCAGACCCAGACUCUUUCCACAGACCCAUGCUGUCUCUCUUGGCACCUUAUUUUUCUGUCGUGGUGAUGUUAUUGUUUGUCUUAUUUGGCAAUGUUUACACCGGAGGAGUAGAGGCCAUUGUGUGUUGGUGGCGUCUGGAAAUACACAAGAGAGUCCCAGGAGAAUGCCACUGUCGGUUCUUACCACAAUUAGCAAUUGUCAGGUCAGGGGCAGUGAUUGGGUCGGUGUCACUCUCUACAUGGCUGGCUCUGCGUGUUGAAACACCACUGCCUGUACCUCCACAGAUGCCAAAGGGAGUGUGGGUCCUAGGACUACAGCCCCAUUUCUACCCAGCCCUGGCUAUCUCUCCACUCAGAUCUAGGUCCUUUCUGUUCAGGAAAACGUCCUGUUUGUGUAGCCUGCUAGACAGCAAAGGCAAGUGCCAAUCAGCUGGAUGAUCUCUCUGGGCCUCAGUUUCCCCAUCUUCACAAUGGACUAGUAAGUGGGAACCAGUCAAAAUUGGCUCAGAGAUCCCCAAUAGGGUUCUAGCUCCAUUGUGAAAUAAAUUUCAAGUGGAGCCUCGUCCUGACUCCUGUUUUCACAUGCUCCCUUAGAGGGAAGGAAGGUGGACGAUUAAAGAUGAUUGGUCGGGAGCUGGAGGAAGGAACUCCCCAUUCUCCAAGAGGAGGUUCUGUUGGAAUAGAGGGGCAGAGACUUGGAAGUCGCUGUUGGGCAUGGCCCAACCCACUUCCAUGACAGCAGCAAGACCACCACCCUCAAGAAGGAGGUGGGCUGGGGUACGAGAAGGUGGGCUGCCCAGUGGUUUCUACAAAAAGGGAUAGUUGUGCUUGCAGGAGGGGUAGUGUCUCCAUCUCCUGAUGCCAGGGAGAAGGAGGCAGGCUGCUGGGGUGACGGAGAGCACCCUCAACUAGGUCACACUGCACUCCCUCUGUGCCUCAGUUUCCACUUCUGUUAGAUGGCUGAUAUGAUCUCUGCCCUGCCAGUUGGAUUGGGGCUUCCAAAAUAUCAACUACUGCAAAAGAAGAGGUUGUGGCCACUGUGACUCAUAUACAUGUACAUGAACGUAUCUGAAGUUUUCAGGGCUGAUACUGAUGUGAGGCAACCCAUGCAGGCAACCCGGAGGAACUGUGUCCCUCACUCUGAGACAGUGAGAACGGACUGAGCCGGAAAGCUGAUGGCCGUGAGAGGAGCAGGUUUGAAAAUCACUGAAUGAAGUCAUGUUGUACAGAGGGGGCGGGGGUGCAUACUGUGGGACGGAGGUGAGUCACAGUGCAUAAGUGUUGGGGAGUCACCUUGAACUUGGGCCAGAAGAGUAGAAAUAUUGAGACUUGGGUUUAUCUGCCUCACAUCAGGUACAUCAAGUUCUGGAUGGCUGCCCACUGGCCAGAGACAUGAGGUGGACGGCUCCCUUUUGCUGCCCUGGGAAGGCCUUCUGCUGGCUUCGGCCCCACUGAGCAAAGUCUGCUUGUUCACUGGAGUUCACACAGACUCCUUGCCAGGCCUGCCCAGAAUCCUGUCUCCUCUGACUUCCUGUGCUCUUGCAUAAUAUUUCCUUGCUCCCUGAAUGGCUGGCCCCAGUGCAGGAGCAGCUCACUCACACUGCUGGACCGAGGGCAGGAUGUAGAGGGAGGGCAGGGAUCUGCAAACGUCACCCAGGGGUGCUCUGGGCUCUGAGGGUGGAGGGCAAGAGGGGCAGAGCCCCCUCAAAUUCUUUGGAAGAUUAUAGCACAAGGGGAGUUGGGAAGGCCCUGGGACCAUGUGCACACACAUCUAUCUCCAUGAAUUGUCUCUCCUGUAAAAUUAUUUUUAAAGUUGCUAAGUUGUUUUCUUCUGAUUAUAAAAAAUAUACAUGUUCCCCAUAAAAAGUCAUAGUAAAAGAAGGCAUGGAGAUAAAAAUAAAAAUCACCAAAAUUCCAUCACCCAGAGAUAACCACUGUUAACUCUUUGGUGAACAUACUUUUCUCUAUAUCAUGAAUAUUGAUAUAUAAUUACAGAAUACGGGCAUACUUCUAAGAUAUUGUAGGUUCGUUCCAGGCCACUACAGUAAAGUGAAUAUCACAAUAAAACGAGUCACAUGAUUUUUUUUUGUUUCCUCGUGCAUAUGAAAGUUAUGUUUAUAUUUUAGCAUUAUGUCUAAAAAACAAUGUACAUACCCUUUUUUUUUUUCUUUUUGAGACACAGUUUCACUCCGUUGCACAGACUGGAGUGCAAUGGGGCAAUCUUAGCUCACUGCAACUUCCGCCUCCUGGGUUCAAGCAAUUCUGGUGCCUCAGCACCCCCGAGUAGCUGGGAUUUACAGACAUGUGCUGCCACACCCAGCUAAUUUUUGUGUUUUUAGUAGAGAUGGGGUUUUGCCAUGUUGGCCAGGCUGGUCUCGAACUACUGGCCUCAAAUGAUCUGCCUGCCUCAGCCUCCCAAAGUGUUGGGAUUACAGGCAUGAGCCACCGCACCUGGCCAACAAUGUCUAUACCUUAAUUUAAAAAUAUUUUAUUGCUAAAAGAAAUGCUAACAAUCAUCUGAGCCUUCAGUGAGUCAUAAUCUUCUUACUGGGAGAGGUUCUUGCCUCCAUAUCGGUGGCUGCAGAACUGAUUAGUGUGACGGUUGCUGAAGGUUGGGGUGGCUGUGGCAAUUCCUUGAAAUCAGACAAGAAUGAAGUUUUUUACAUCAAUAGAGUCUUCUUUUCAGGAAAGACUCUGCAGCAUGUGAUACUGUCUGAUAGCAUUUUACCCACAGUAAAACUUCCUUCAUAAUUGGUGUCAAUCCUCUCAAACCCUGCCACUGCUUUAUCAACUUAGUUGAUGUAAUAUUCUAAAUCCUUUGUUGUCAUUUCCACAGUGUUCACACCAUCUUUACCAGGAGCAAAUUCCAUCUUGAGAAGCCACUUUUCUUUUCUCAUCUGUAAGAAGCUCUGACUCAUCUGUUCAAGUUUUAUCAUGAGGUUGCAACAGUUCAGUCACAUCUUCAGGCUCCACUUCUAGUUUUCUUGCUAUUUCUUCCACAUCUGCAGUUACUUCCUCCACUAAAGUCUUGAACCCCUCAAAGUCAUCCGUGAGGUUUGGAAUUAACUUCUUCCAGACUCCUGUUACUGCUGAUAUUUUGACAUCCUCCCACAAAUUACAAAUGCUGUUAAUGGUAUCUAGAAUGGUGAACUCUUUUCAGGUGGUUUUCAAUUUACUUUGCCCAGAUUCAUCUAGGAAUCACUAUCUAUGGCAGCUAUAGCCUUACAAAAUUUCUUGAAUAAGACUUGGAAGUCAGAAUUACUCCUUGAUCCAUGGGCUUCAGAAUGGAUCUUGUGUUAGCAGGCAUGAAAACAACAUUAAUUUUGUGCGUCUCCAUCAGGGCUCUUGAGUAACUAGGUGCAUUGACAACGAGCACAUAAACAUAUGUGCUGUCAUCCAGGUUUUGUUGUUCCACUGAUAGAGCACCAAUAAAGUAGAUUUGGCAUAAUUUUUAAGAACCCUAGGACUUACAGAAUGGUAAAUGAUAAGUGGCUUCAGCUUAAACUCACCAGCUGCAUUAGUCCCUAGUAAGAGAGUCAGCCUGUCCUUUGAAACUAGGGAUUGACUUCUCCCCUCUUGCAGUGAAAGUCCUAGAUGGCAUGUUCAUCCAGCAUAAGGCUCUUUCAUCUACACUGAAAAUCUGUUUAGUGUAGCCACCUUCAUCAAUGAUCUUAGCUAGAUCUUCUAAAUAACUGGCUGCCGCUUAUGUAUCAGCACUUGCUCUUUCACCUUGCAUUUUUAUGUUAUGGAGAUGUCUUCUUUCCUUAAAUGUGACGAACCAACCUCUGCUAGCUUCAUACUUUUCUUAAUGCAGCUUCCUUACCUUGCUCUGCCUUCCUAGAAUUGAAGAGAGUUAGGGCCUUGCUCUGGAUUAGACUUUGGCUUAAGGGAAUAUUAUGCCUGGUUUGAUCUUCUCACUAAGCUUAAUCAUUCCUUAACUUUUGAUUUAAAGUGAGAGAUGUGACUCUUCCUUUCAUUCGAACACAUAGAGCCCAUUGUAGAGUUAUUAAAAUUGGUCUAAUUUCAAUAUUGUUGUGUCUCAGGGAAUAGGAAGGAUUGGGGAGGGGGAGAGAGAGAUACACACACACACACACAAACACACACACGCACACAGAGGAACAAUCACUGGACCAGUCAGAACACACACAACAUUUAUUAAGAUCACUGUCUUAUAUGGGUGCAGUUUAUGCCUAAAAACAAUUACGGUGGUAACAUCAAAGAUCACUGAUCGCAGAUCAUUAUAAUAAUAGCUAUAAUAAUGAAAGUUUGAAAUAUUGCAAGAAUGACCAAAAUGUGGCACAGAUAUGAAGUGAGCACAUACUAUUGGAAAAAUGGCAUGGAUAAACUUGCCUGACAAACCUUCAAUUUGUAAAAAGUGCAAUAUCUGCAAAGUGCAAUAAAGUAAGGCAUAAUAAAACAAGGCAUGCCUGUGUUUCUUAACCAUUUAACACGUGUAAAACUGUGCUACCAUUUUUAUUAAGUUCCCAUAUUGUUUUUGUGUUGCUGAGAAAGUUUUUGAGUGUUGUACCCUAACCUCUUCUUUCCCGUAAGCUCUGUGGUUUUUAGUUUUGCAUAGUGUGGUGAUUUUUAGGAGCUCAUAUGCCAUGUUGUAGCAGAACUACUUGUAAAUUCACAUGACGUGUCUUCCCUAAAUUCAACAUUAAUUAUUAGUUAUUAAUAGUAUUAAUUGUGAAGCACAAUAAAAUGAGGUAUGCCUGCAUUAUCAUGUUACAUGCUAUUGUGAAAUGCAUUUUCUAUAUAGCAAUAUAUCAGAACUAUCUCUUGCUACUAAGUUACAAAGAUUUAAUACAUAGUUGUAUUAAGUUCCACUUAUAGAGGUAUCAUAGUGAAACCCUUAUUCAUUGACAUGUCCAGGCUCAGAAAACAAGCUAUAACCAGCCCAAGCUUAUUUUCAGACCUGAAAAGCAGCAUCUUUUCUAUAUUUCUGACCAAUGUGUUAUCUGAAAAGCGGCAUCUUUUCUAUAUUUCUGACCAGUGUGUUAGCUAUGGUGCCCCAGAAAUAGCUGCAAAAUAAAAGGUUAAGUGCCAUGUAGGCCUUUCUCUAGGCUUAGAAUAAUUCACUUGAUUACAUAGGAAGAGGCUGCAAUGAUGACAGCUUCCAGGGCUGGGCCAGACCUUACCCUGGGUAAAAUGAUCCUCCAGUGUGGCCCAUAUGUAUGCUUUGAGCCAGGAGCUGCUAGCUGGGAGAACAAGUUUUUCUUCAGUGGUAUUCCUGUGACCAAGAUUUCAAAUAAGCUCCAUUUUUAAUUUUAAUUGGUUAUUGUCCUCCUGAAAUUUUAUGACACAAUCUAUAUCUUUAAAAAGGCACUCUUUCUUCUUUAUACAGUUGUUUUCAUGAUGUUAAAAACUUUAAAGAAAGUAUCAUUCAGAUUUGCUGACAGUUGGAAGAUUAUUUUAAAAAUCCAACUAGUUUAGCUGAAAAAGGUGCUAUCAGUGUUUCUGUCUCAUCCUUGGAAAUUGUAUAUUUUUAAGGCUUGUGAUUAGCUUUUUCUCCUCCAUUGCUGAUCGUGGUUGGAAGUGUGGCAUAGAUUUACAGUAAACUUUGAUAUAAUGGUGAUUCCUCUUUGUUUUGGAGCCAGGUGCCUGCGGUAUUUGCUUAUUUUCUUUGAUUCAUUUUUAAAUUGAGUUGAAUGUUUGAUUUAAUCAGAAGUGAUAGUAUGAGGCUGGGGAUGAUUGCUUGUGGUUGGGAAUUGCUUGUAAAGUUUACUGUUUAGUCAAGACAAAUCGUUUCCUAAAGCUCUCUUUUUCAGAUUUCUUGUCUAUGUGGGAAAGCAUGAUAAUGCCAGUCAGUUUAAACAUAUUUAAGAGUUCCCAGGCAUCUUCGAACAGAAAAAUUUGCAACAAAAUUUGGCAACGGCAGAAUGCGAGGAUUUUUGCCUCAUUUUGUUUAUAGUUGUCUGCUCUUCAGGCAAAUGAUCUAUUACAACAAUCUGAAUAAUUACAGUCUCUCCUUCAAUUUAUUCACCCUGGACUCCUUUUUCUAGAAUUACUGGCCAGACUCUUAUUACACCAAAUUCCUUGACUCUAUUCCCGAGGAAUGAGGAUGGGACUAGGAGUAAAAGUUAAAGAGAGAAACUAAUUGUUGCCUGCUUUUCAAAGUUUUCGGUGUGUGGAAAUUUGUUGAUUUUGUAAUUGCUCCCUUAGUUGGUCAUUACCCGAUUCUGGUAGGGUACUUGCCAUGUGUACACAUUUAGGGAGUGCAAAGGGACAGUAAGACUUAAUUGGUCCUGGGAAUUGUUGAACAGGACUUUGUUGAAAUGGCUACUUCUGUACAAUGCACAUGGAGCAGCUGUUGGCAUAGCAACUCCUACGUGGAAAAGUGCACGCCGCUUGCAGAUGACUUUUGCAGUGCUCAGUGUUAAUUUGAUAAAUGGCUUUUCUAAUAGCAGUUUGUGGGCUAAUGGAAAGAUCGAAGCAAACCUUCAUUAACGGAAAGGAGAAUAGGGAUUUUGAAGCCACUGGGUGAACACACUGGACAGCCAGAGCUAAAUCUCCAUUUUCAGCUGUGUCUCUUUUUCACAGCAGAUAUGCUUGGAGUGUGGCAGAUGAAAGUAAAUUAAGAAAACUGUCUGCCCGUGCCAUUAUCAUCUUAGAUUUUAAGCAGGGAGAGGUUUUGGAGUCCUUUCUAUUCAAGAUACUUAACUUUGUGUGAGAGUUUAGUUUAAGAGUACUGUAGAAGCUUUGCAUUGUGUUGUCGUUUUCCUUUGCUGGUAGUGGUGGGGUUAAGGUGGUUAAAUCGUUUUUUAUUGUGGUAAAAUAUACAUAACAAAAAAUGUUUACCAUUUUAACUAUUUUUAAGCCUGCAAUUCAAUGGCAUUAAGUACGUUCAUAUUGUUGGGCUACAAGCACCACUGCUCAAGAACUUUUUCAUCAUCUCAAAUGGAAACUCUGUACUCAUUAAAUAAUAACUCUUUAUUCCCCACAUGCUCCAAUCCCCGAUAAUCACUAUUCUACUUUCUCUAUGAAUAUGACUAUUCCAAGUAGAUUGUAUAUAUAGACAUAUAAAGUAUUUGUCCUUUUAUGUCUGGCUUAUUUCACUUAGCAUAAUGUUUUCAAGGUUCAUCCAAGUUACAACAUGUAUUCAAAGUUUUAUUUCUUUUUAAGGCCGAAUAAUAUCCUAUUGUGUGUAGACACUAUAUUUUGUUUAUCUGGUCUUCUGUCAAGGGACAUUUGAGUUGUUUCCACCUUUGGGUGUUGUGAAUCAUGGUGAACAUGGUGUACAAUUUGAGUCCCUGCUUUCAGUUUUUUUGGAUAUAGACCUAGAAGUGGAAUUUCUGGAUCAUAUGGUAAUUCUGUGUUUAUUUUUUUCAAAAACUGCUGUACUGUCUUCCAUAGCAGCCAUACCAUUGUACAUUUUCACGAGCAAUGCAUAAGAGUUCCAGUUUCUUCAUUUCCCUGCUAACACUUGUUAUUUUCUGUUUUUUGUUUUGUUUUGUUUUUGUUUUUAGAUAUCAGCCAUCCUAGUGGGUGUGAAGUGGUAUCUCAUUGUGGCUUUGAUUUACAUUUUCCUAAUGAUCAGUGAUUUGUCUUUAUAAACAUAUUGCCUGUUCCUUGCCCCCCACCCCACCCCCGCACCCCCACAACAGCCUGUGUGGGAAUGGAAAUCACUGCCCCAUUGUUUACACCUGUGAGGCAAACAAAGACUAUCAACAUAAUGAUAUUUGGGAGUGAAAGGUGUCAGGGAGAGAAGGAUGAAGGCACCAUAAGGUUAUUAUAUAUAAUAACUGGCAUAUAGGAUAUAGUACAGGCACCUCAGUAGACCUAUUUUCAGUUCGUGCUGUGGAGCAUGUGAAACUAUUUUAAAUAGAGGCCUUUGGGACUUAAGUAACUUCAACUCUCUGAAUGAGGUUUAAGGCAAGCUUGCUGUGGGCUGGAUCUAUCCUGUAUAAUCCCUACUGAUUUGGGUGAUGUAUAGGUACCCUUCCCUGAAAUUCUUCCCUGAGAAUAAUUAUUGUUGUCAUCUACUACGGAAUCCUGGGCCCACUUUCUUCCUUCUUCUUGGGGGAGGAAAUCUCCCAGACAUCUUGCCAAGCAUUUGCUUAAGUCUUUGAACCGCUGCACUAGCUAAUUUCUCCACCUGAAACAAUAUACAAACCCCUCCUCUUCUCCACCCGCUAGGUUCUUAUGCUGGCAGCUCAUAUUUUUACAAGAAAAAGAAGUUAGAAUGUAUUGAGCACCUGCUAUAAGCCUGGCACUUUGCUAGUCACUGUGUGGCAGAUGACUACAUCAGUCAUGACUGAUAAAACAUAACUUCUAUCCUUGUAAGUGCCGCAGGACUUAUUUGUGACUCUUAACAACAGGGGUUCCAAACCUUAGUGUGCAUCAGAACUGCCUGGGGCUUAUUAAAACUCAGAUUACUGGACCUCAUCCCUAGAAUUUCUUACUCGGCCCGCAGGUCUGAGGUGGAGCCUGAGAGUGUGCAUUUCUAACAAGUUCCUAGAUGAUGAUGAUGUUGCUCAUCCCUGGACCACACUAUGAGAACCACUGCUUUCCAUCAAGCCUGUGAAAUAGAUAUUAUUCCCAUUUAUAGAUGAGGAGCUGAGAUGUAGAGAGGCCAAAUGACUUGCCUCAGUUCUUGCACACAGAGCCAGAGCCCAGAUUUGAAGCUGAGAGGCCUCACUCCAAAGCUUCUGCUGUUUCCAUUAUAUCAGGGAUGGCAAAGGCAUAGAUACCACCUGUGCUUCCCUCACUUAGUCCACCCCCACGACAGGCAAUAUUAAUCAAUCACAGCACCUCUGAGCCCAGAGAUGUCCUCGGAAUCUUUCACACACUGCUCCUGACAGCCAAACCUACCCGUCAGUGGGAGCUGAAGUUUGCAAUUUCUGUACUAACCUGUAUGGCCUUUCUAAAAUGGAGACAUUACCAAGGAAUCAAUCUAUUAACAGCUGAAAACAAACCUUGUGUGAGCUCCAGUCUUAUCUGCCUAGGAGGGAAGAGCGUGGUAGAUUGCAGGCUGUGUGAAGCACAGCACUCCCAUGGCGACCUCACGGAUCAUAACUAGAGUCUACACUCAGCACACAGGCAACACAGGGCCGUUACCCUUGAAAAGUGUAAAAAUCUAGACGAAGUUAAUGAGGAGACUUUUUUUUUAAGCUGCUAUAUUUUGUCUAAUUCAUAUAUGCUACAUUUUAUUCUAAAAAUAGUUAUUCUACUCUUUGGCACUAAGUUUGGUGAUGGAUAUAAAAUAGUGAUCAAUAAACAGUUGUUAAGAAAGGAAAAAUAAAGUAGGUGCCAAAGGCAACUGUGUCCACACCUGAUGAGGUCUUUUAACAAAUGGAUGGGAGGAAUAAACAAGACUGAAUUAUGUUUUUAUAUAUCUUGCGCACCCAACAGUUCUUAGCAAGGCCCGUGGGCAGUAGAUGCCCAAUAAAUAUUUAUCAUACGGAACUACAAAUCUUGCUUGUGAAAGUACAAAGCAUAGGUGUAUCCUGGAGGUAGGGAACAGUAACCCUGAGAGCAGACUGGUUUAAGGCCAUCUCUGGCCAAACCAAAACACAUUACAGAGGCUCUCUGAGUCCCAAAGUCAUCCACAGAUUGAUGUCUUGCUUCUCUUCUUAUGGCAUAAGAGACUGGUAGAAAACUGACCAAACUCAUCAAGAAAGUAAUAUUUUUUUUUCCUCUGAAAAUUGUGAAUUGUAUCAGAUAUUGCCACUAUUAUGCCCCUAGGUCACUUGCUCAUCUGUUUUCCACAGGGAAGCCAAAACAGAAUUUUGCAAAGAUAUACAUGAGUAAUCAAAGGAAACUGACUGUAUUGGGUGUGAUUCUCCUGUCUUCUGAAAUAACCCACCAUGAUCUUUUGCGUGUUUCUGCCAGCCCAUACAAUGUCUGGUCUCACCACCAACAACAAAUAUUUAGUCUAUGGCUACUGUGUAUAUAGGGCAACCUCUUGUCUCAUUUGCUGUUUGUGCAGCUUAAAAGCAAGGGCAGGGUGAAUUAUGGUUUUUUUGUUUGUUUGUUUUUGAGACGGAGUCUCGUUCUGUAGCCCAGGCUGGAGUGCGGUGGUGCGAUCUUGGCUCACUGCAAGCUCCGCCUUCUGGGUUCAUGCCAUUCUCCUUCCUCACCCUCCUGAGUAGCUGGGACUACAGGCACCCGCCACCACGCCUGGCUAAUUUUUUUGUAUUUUUAGUAGAAACAGAGUUUCACCACGUUAGCCAGGAUGGUCUCGAUCUUCUGACCUUGUGAUCUGCCCACCUCGGCCUCCCAAGGUGCUAGGAUUACAGGUGUGAGCCACUGCGCCCAGCCCUAAUUAUGUUUUUAUAUGAAUUGCACACCCCACAGUUCUUAGCAAGGCCCAUGGGCAAUAGAUGCCCAAUAAAUAUUUAUCAUCCAAAACUACAAAUCUUGCUUGUGAAAAUACAAAGCAUAGGUGCAUGCUGGAGGUAGGGAACAGUAACCCUGAGAACAGACUGGUUUAAGGCCAUCUCUGGCCAAACCAAGACACAGUUAAAGGGAGCAUUUAUGUCCCUGUUUGGCUGUGAUAUGCCCUAUAGACUGGGGCAAGGCUGUGGCAGCCUGGCCAGGAUGAAAACGCUCAUCCUUGGGCUGCCCCUAGAUGCCAAACUUUUUCCGUACAAGUUUUCAAGGCACAUUAUUAAAAGCAGUUACGUAAGUGGGGAACUAACUGCACCUUAUAAAAGGCUUAACAGGAGAGACAGAGUCCUCCAUUUGGAGCUGUUUUGUUAAAUGUUGAGAAUAGAGAAGUCCAGAAGUGGUUGGUGUUUCUGCUCUACACUGAAAACGAAUUGGGCUGGAGCCCAUCUCACAGCCUGCCUUUCUUUCUUCUAUCUCACCCAGCUUGGGCACAGGCUUUUGCUAUACUGUUGGACUGGGCAGUUCCCCAUUGAUAGAGAUGUUGUUUAAUAUUUAAGUAUGUUGUGUAGCUCUUAACAUCGAAAGAGAAGAAAAAAGGUCCAGUUUAUCUUUAGGGUGAGCUGACCUUUCCAGAUGGAGCAGGGAAAUCUCCUGAGGACAGGACCCUGGGAGGAAUCCACUUCCCUGCUUAAAAAGCAUGGUGAGGAAGGUUCCCUUGGGCUUGUUGGAUCCAGUACUCUCCAGUGGGCAGUGCUCUGUAUGUUCUAGGUUAGAGUCUUAGAUAAUAUGGGAUUUUAAAACCAGUAUUGUAUUACAUUAGAGUAUUACUGCCCUUGGGAAUUUUUUAGAUAGUUCCUUUUGGGGAGAGAACUGUUUUGUCCUAUCCAUUGCAGAUGGGAGCAAGAACAUACAAAAGAGCAUAAAGAAAAAUUCUGCCGAUGUGGGCAUUUCCUUGAGGCUGAGGGACUAGGAGAGGCACCAAAGGGUGUCCUUCAUUCAUGGUAAAAGCCCUAAUAGCCUCAGUGUUAGAAUAUCCUGUAGGCAGGCGAAGGAUGACAUGACUCACUUUGGUGGUGACCUCCUAGUAGUUCAACUGAGAAUCCAGGCGGGAUAAGAUCAGUGCAGGGUAAUUGUAUGGUAGCUAGUCAACCUUUCCAUUGCUUAGCCGGAGAAUUCUGGCUUUUGUGCUGGUGAUGUCAGGCAGGUGUUGGAGGAGGAGUUCCAUGACCAUUUUCUCUGUUCCUGCCAACAGGAAAGCUCCAUUGGGACAUACACGCUCACUUCCAGGGUGUUUUAUAUUCAUCCAUAGCUGCUGCAUGGAUAAAAAAUUUGGCGAAAAACUUGAAAUCCUAUUACCAUGAUGAUCAUUAGAACUCAUGUUAGGGCUUUUUGUUUUUAAAACAGGGACACAAAGAAGAAACAGAAGGCUGCCAUAUGCAAGGAGUAGCUCGGAGAGGAGGAAGGAGAAGUCCCGGGAUGCUGCGCGGUGCCGGCGGAGCAAGGAGACGGAGGUGUUCUAUGAGCUGGCCCAUGAGCUGCCUCUGCCCCACAGUGUGAGCUCCCAUCUGGACAAGGCCUCCAUCAUGCGACUGGCAAUCAGCUUCCUGCGAACACACAAGCUCCUCUCCUCAGUUUGCUCUGAAAACGAGUCCGAAGCCGAAGCUGACCAGCAGAUGGACAACUUGUACCUGAAAGCCUUGGAGGGUUUCAUUGCCGUGGUGACCCAAGAUGGCGACAUGAUCUUUCUGUCAGAAAACAUCAGCAAGUUCAUGGGACUUACACAGGUGGAGCUAACAGGACAUAGUAUCUUUGACUUCACUCAUCCCUGCGACCAUGAGGAGAUUCGUGAGAACCUGAGUCUCAAAAAUGGCUCUGGUUUUGGGAAAAAAAGCAAAGACAUGUCCACAGAGCGGGACUUCUUCAUGAGGAUGAAGUGCACGGUCACCAACAGAGGCCGUACUGUCAACCUCAAGUCAGCCACCUGGAAGGUCUUGCACUGCACGGGCCAGGUGAAAGUCUACAACAACUGCCCUCCUCACAAUAGUCUGUGUGGCUACAAGGAGCCCCUGCUGUCCUGCCUCAUCAUCAUGUGUGAACCAAUCCAGCACCCAUCCCACAUGGACAUCCCCCUGGAUAGCAAGACCUUCCUGAGCCGCCACAGCAUGGACAUGAAGUUCACCUACUGUGAUGACAGAAUCACAGAACUGAUUGGUUACCACCCUGAGGAGCUGCUUGGCCGCUCAGCCUAUGAAUUCUACCAUGCGCUAGACUCCGAGAACAUGACCAAGAGUCACCAGAACUUGUGCACCAAGGGUCAGGUAGUAAGUGGCCAGUACCGGAUGCUCGCAAAGCAUGGGGGCUACGUGUGGCUGGAGACCCAGGGGACGGUCAUCUACAACCCUCGCAACCUGCAGCCCCAGUGCAUCAUGUGUGUCAACUACGUCCUGAGUGAGAUUGAGAAGAAUGACGUGGUGUUCUCCAUGGACCAGACUGAAUCCCUGUUCAAGCCCCACCUGAUGGCCAUGAACAGCAUCUUUGAUAGCAGUGGCAAGGGGGCUGUGUCUGAGAAGAGUAACUUCCUAUUCACCAAGCUAAAGGAGGAGCCCGAGGAGCUGGCCCAGCUGGCUCCCACCCCAGGAGACGCCAUCAUCUCUCUGGAUUUCGGGAAUCAGAACUUCGAGGAGUCCUCAGCCUAUGGCAAGGCCAUCCUGCCCCCGAGCCAGCCAUGGGCCACGGAGUUGAGGAGCCACAGCACCCAGAGCGAGGCUGGGAGCCUGCCUGCCUUCACCGUGCCCCAGGCAGCUGCCCCGGGCAGCACCACCCCCAGUGCCACCAGCAGCAGCAGCAGCUGCUCCACGCCCAAUAGCCCUGAAGACUAUUACACAUCUUUGGAUAACGACCUGAAGAUUGAAGUGAUUGAGAAGCUCUUCGCCAUGGACACAGAGGCCAAGGACCAAUGCAGUACCCAGACGGAUUUCAAUGAGCUGGACUUGGAGACACUGGCACCCUAUAUCCCCAUGGACGGGGAAGACUUCCAGCUAAGCCCCAUCUGCCCCGAGGAGCGGCUCUUGGCGGAGAACCCACAGUCCACCCCCCAGCACUGCUUCAGUGCCAUGACAAACAUCUUCCAGCCACUGGCCCCUGUAGCCCCGCACAGUCCCUUCCUCCUGGACAAGUUUCAGCAGCAGCUGGAGAGCAAGAAGACAGAGCCCGAGCACCGGCCCAUGUCCUCCAUCUUCUUUGAUGCCGGAAGCAAAGCAUCCCUGCCACCGUGCUGUGGCCAGGCCAGCACCCCUCUCUCUUCCAUGGGGGGCAGAUCCAAUACCCAGUGGCCCCCAGAUCCACCAUUACAUUUUGGGCCCACAAAGUGGGCCGUCGGGGAUCAGCGCACAGAGUUCUUGGGAGCAGCGCCGUUGGGGCCCCCUGUCUCUCCACCCCAUGUCUCCACCUUCAAGACAAGGUCUGCAAAGGGUUUUGGGGCUCGAGGCCCAGACGUGCUGAGUCCGGCCAUGGUAGCCCUCUCCAACAAGCUGAAGCUGAAGCGACAGCUGGAGUAUGAAGAGCAAGCCUUCCAGGACCUGAGCGGGGGGGACCCACCUGGUGGCAGCACCUCACAUUUGAUGUGGAAACGGAUGAAGAACCUCAGGGGUGGGAGCUGCCCUUUGAUGCCGGACAAGCCACUGAGCGCAAAUGUACCCAAUGAUAAGUUCACCCAAAACCCCAUGAGGGGCCUGGGCCAUCCCCUGAGACAUCUGCCGCUGCCACAGCCUCCAUCUGCCAUCAGUCCCGGGGAGAACAGCAAGAGCAGGUUCCCCCCACAGUGCUACGCCACCCAGUACCAGGACUACAGCCUGUCGUCAGCCCACAAGGUGUCAGGCAUGGCAAGCCGGCUGCUCGGGCCCUCAUUUGAGUCCUACCUGCUGCCCGAACUGACCAGAUAUGACUGUGAGGUGAACGUGCCCGUGCUGGGAAGCUCCACGCUCCUGCAAGGAGGGGACCUCCUCAGAGCCCUGGACCAGGCCACCUGAGCCAGGCCUUCUACCUGGGCAGCACCUCUGCCGACGCCGUCCCACCAGCUUCACUCUCUCCGUCUGUUUUUGCAACUAGGUAUUUCUAACGCCAGCACACUAUUUACAAGAUGGACUUACCUGGCAGACUUGCCCAGGUCACCAAGCAGUGGCCUUUUUCUGAGAUGCUCACUUUAUUAUCCCUAUUUUUAAAGUACACAAUUGUUUUACCUGUUCUGAAAUGUUCUUAAAUUUUGUAGGAUUUUUUUCCUCCCCACCUUCAAUGACUUCUAAUUUAUAUUAUCCAUAGGUUUCUCUCCCUCCUUCUCCUUCUCACACACAACUGUCCAUACUAACAAGUUUGGUGCAUGUCUGUUCUUCUGUAGGGAGAAGCUUUAGCUUCAUUUUACUAAAAAGAUUCCUCGUUAUUGUUGUUGCCAAAGAGAAACAAAAAUGAUUUUGCUUUCCAAGCUUGGUUUGUGGCGUCUCCCUCGCAGAGCCCUUCUCGUUUCUUUUUUAAACUAAUCACCAUAUUGUAAAUUUCAGGGUUUUUUUUUUUUUGUUUAAGCUGACUCUUUGCUCUAAUUUUGGAAAAAAAGAAAUGUGAAGGGUCAACUCCAACGUAUGUGGUUAUCUGUGAAAGUUGCACAGCGUGGCUUUUCCUAAACUGGUGUUUUUCCCCCGCAUUUGGUGGAUUUUUUAUUAUUAUUCAAAAACAUAACUGAGUUUUUUAAAAGAGGAGAAAAUUUAUAUCUGGGUUAAGUGUUUAUCAUAUAUAUGGGUACUUUGUAAUAUCUAAAAACUUAGAAACGGAAAUGGAAUCCUGCUCACAAAAUCACUUUAAGAUCUUUUCGAAGCUGUUAAUUUUUCUUAGUGUUGUGGACACUGCAGACUUGUCCAGUGCUCCCACGGCCUGUACGGACACUGUGGAAGGCCUCCCUCUGUCGGCUUUUUGCCAUCUGUGAUAUGCCAUAGGUGUGACAAUCCGAGCAGUGGAGUCAUUCAGCGGGAGCACUGCGCGCUAUCCCCUCACAUUCUCUAUGUACUAUGUAUGUAUGUAUUAUUAUUAUUGCUGCCAAGAGGGUCUGAUGGCACGUUGUGGGGUCGGGGGGUGGGGCGGGGAAGUGCUCUAACUUUUCUUAAGGUUUUGUUGCUAGCCCUUCAAGUGCACUGAGCUAUGUGACUCGGAUGGUCUUUCACACGGCACAUUUGGACAUUUCCAGAACUACCAUGAGAUGGUUUAGACGGGAAUUCAUGCAAAUGAGGGGUCAAAAAUGGUAUAGUGACCCCGUCCACGUCCUCCAAGCUCACGACCUUGGAGCCCCGUGGAGCUGGACUGAGGAGGAGGCUGCACAGCGGGAGAGCAGCUGGUCCAGACCAGCCCUGCAGCCCCCACUCAGCCGGCAGCCAGAUGGCCCCGCAAGGCCUCCAGGGAUGGCCCCUAGCCACAGGCCCUGGCUGAGGUCUCUGGGUCGGUCAGUGACAUGUAGGUAGGAAGCACUGAAAAUAGUGUUCCCAGAGCACUUUGCAACUCCCUGGGUAAGAGGGACGACACCUCUGGUUUUUCAAUACCAAUUACAUGGAACUUUUCUGUAAUGGGUACAAUGAAGAAGUUUCUAAAAACACACACAAAGCACAUUGGGCCAACUAUUUAGUAAGCCCGGAUAGACUUAUUGCCAAAAACAAAAAAUAGCUUUCAAAAGAAAUUUAAGUUCUAUGAGAAAUUCCUUAGUCAUGGUGUUGCGUAAAUCAUAUUUUAGCUGCACGGCAUUACCCCACACAGGGUGGCAGAACUUGAAGGGUUACUGACGUGUAAAUGCUGGUAUUUGAUUUCCUGUGUGUGUUGCCCUGGCAUUAAGGGCAUUUUACCCUUGCAGUUUUACUAAAACACUGAAAAAUAUUCCAAGCUUCAUAUUAACCCUACCUGUCAACGUAACGAUUUCAUGAACGUUAUUAUAUUGUCGAAUUCCUACUGACAACAUUAUAACUGUAUGGGAGCUUAACUUUAUAAGGAAAUGUAUUUUGACACUGGUAUCUUAUUAAAGUAUUCUGAUCCUA